CUUUUGCCUCGGAACUGGACCCGGGAGACAUCACAGCGCUGGGCUAGGGGCGCGGCUUGAACUCGCCUAAAGAGCUGCGCCCUCUCAUCUCGCGCCUGCAGCCCGUGCCGCCCCAGCCGCUGCCGCCUGCACCGGACCCGGAGCCGUCAUGCCCAAGUGUCCCAAGUGCAACAAGGAGGUGUACUUCGCCGAGAGGGUGACCUCUCUGGGCAAGGACUGGCAUCGGCCCUGCCUGAAGUGCGAGAAAUGUGGGAAGACGCUGACCUCUGGGGGCCACGCUGAGCACGAAGGCAAACCCUACUGCAACCACCCCUGCUACGCAGCCAUGUUUGGGCCUAAAGGCUUUGGGCGGGGCGGAGCCGAGAGCCACACUUUCAAGUAAACCAGGUGGUGGAGACCCCAUCCUUGGCUGCUUGCAGGGCCACUGUCCAGGCAAAUGCCAGGCCUUGUCCCCAGAUGCCCAGGGCUCCCUUGUUGCCCCUAAUGCUCUCAGUAAACCUGAACACUUGGAAAACCUGUGUGUGUACAUGCGCGUGUGUGCUGGGGAGUGCCAAGGGAGCUGCAGUGGGGUCCUGGCAGCAGGCUCUGCCACCGGCGCCUGCUCUUCUGCUGCCCAUUGCCCUCCCCAGGGGGCCGUUCCAGGGUCUCAUAGGCGAGGGCUCCCUGUGCAGG